AGUCCAGGCGCCCAGACUCGGCGAAGCGCAGCGCCUGCCACCAGCGGUGCCUCGGGCUGCCCGGCGCGCCGCGCUCCCAGGUUCUGUCUCGCCGCACCCCGGCGGGCACUGGCGCGGGCAAGGACGCUGGCGGGGAGAACGCCCUGGGCUCAACGUACUCCAGAAUCGAAUGUUGAGAGAAGCAGUGCUCUGAUCCAGCUCAGGAGAAAAAGGAGCGGGUUCCGAGUGAGACUUCUGGAGCCAGCUGGACGUGCCGGUUUGCCCAGUGCGGCGCGGCUGCACGCACCGUCCACAAGGUGAGGGGCGCACACCUUCCGGGACGACCUUGGCUUCCCUUCUUACCCCCACCCACUCCAGGAACCUUCACUCAGAAGAAAUGCUGUGGCCCUUCCCUUUACCAACAGAAAAUGGAACACAAGAGACCACAUAGCUGAACAAAUUAUAGCCUCCUUACAAGUGAGAAACCUUCGAGGCUACAUAGUUUUCAGCCAAAGGAAAAUAACCAACAGCUUCUCCACAGUGUAGACUGAAACAAGGGAAACAUGAACAUCACAAACUGUACCACAGAGGCCAGCAUGGCUAUAAGACCCAAGACCAUCACUGAGAAGAUGCUCAUUUGCAUGACUCUGGUGGUCAUCACCACCCUCACCACGUUGCUGAACUUGGCUGUGAUCAUGGCUAUUGGCACCACCAAGAAGCUCCACCAGCCUGCCAACUACCUAAUCUGUUCUCUGGCCGUGACGGACCUCCUGGUGGCAGUGCUCGUCAUGCCCCUGAGCAUCAUCUACAUUGUCAUGGAUCGCUGGAAGCUUGGGUACUUCCUCUGUGAGGUGUGGCUGAGUGUGGACAUGACCUGCUGCACCUGCUCCAUCCUCCACCUCUGUGUCAUUGCCCUGGACAGGUACUGGGCCAUCACCAAUGCUAUUGAAUACGCCAGGAAGAGGACGGCCAAGAGGGCCGCGCUGAUGAUCCUUACCGUCUGGACCAUCUCCAUUUUCAUCUCCAUGCCCCCUCUGUUCUGGAGAAGCCACCGCCGCCUAAGCCCUCCCCCUAGUCAGUGCACCAUCCAGCACGACCAUGUUAUCUACACCAUUUACUCCACGCUGGGUGCGUUUUAUAUCCCCUUGACUUUGAUACUGAUUCUCUAUUACCGGAUUUACCACGCGGCCAAGAGCCUUUACCAGAAAAGGGGAUCAAGUCGGCACUUAAGCAACAGAAGCACAGAUAGCCAGAAUUCUUUUGCAAGUUGUAAACUUACACAGACUUUCUGUGUGUCUGACUUCUCCACCUCAGACCCUACCACAGAGUUUGAAAAGUUCCAUGCCUCCAUCAGGAUCCCCCCCUUCGACAAUGAUCUAGAUCACCCAGGAGAACGUCAGCAGAUCUCUAGCACCAGGGAACGGAAGGCAGCACGCAUCCUGGGGCUGAUUCUGGGUGCAUUCAUUUUAUCCUGGCUGCCAUUUUUCAUCAAAGAGUUGAUUGUGGGUCUGAGCAUCUACACCGUGUCCUCGGAAGUGGCCGACUUUCUGACGUGGCUCGGUUAUGUGAAUUCUCUGAUCAACCCUCUGCUCUAUACGAGUUUUAAUGAAGACUUUAAGCUGGCUUUUAAAAAGCUCAUUAGAUGCCGAGAGCAUACUUAGACUGUAAAAAGCUAAAAGGCACGACUUUUUCCAGAGCCUCAUGAGUGGAUGGGGGUAAGGGGUGCAACUUAUUAAUUCUUGAACAUACUUGGUUCAGGAGAGUUUGUAAGUAUGUGUGGUCUUGUUUCCUUGUUUGUUUGUUUGUUUUGUUCUGUUUUGUUUGAGGAUUGUUAUUUGGCGUGCUGUUUUCUACCUCUGGUCUUAUCUGUGAUACAUAAUUUCAAAUAAACAUUAUCAUACAAAAACA